AGCCGCAGGUUCCCCGCGCGCCCCGAGCCCCCGCGCCAUGAAGCUCGCCGCCCUCCUGGGGCUCUGCGUGGCCCUGUCCUGCAGCUCCGCUGCUGCUUUCUUAGUGGGCUCGGCCAAGCCUGUGGCCCAGCCUGUCGCUGCGCUGGAGUCGGCGGCGGAGGCCGGGGCCGGGACCCUGGCCAACCCCCUCGGCACCCUCAACCCGCUGAAGCUCCUGCUGAGCAGCCUGGGCAUCCCCGUGAACCACCUCAUAGAGGGCUCCCAGAAGUGUGUGGCUGAGCUGGGUCCCCAGGCCGUGGGGGCCGUGAAGGCCCUGAAGGCCCUGCUGGGGGCCCUGACAGUGUUUGGCUGAGCCGAGACUGGAGCAUCUACACCUGAGGACAAGACGCUGCCCACCCGCGAGGGCUGAAAACCCCGCCGCGGGGAGGACCGUCCAUCCCCUUCCCCCGGCCCCUCUCAAUAAACGUGGUUAAGAGCA